AUAUUAGUGCAUUUCUUUGCAGAGGUUACCUCUUUUUCUUGUCUCUCGUCAGGUCUCUGACAUUGACAGAGCCUGGACGUUGGAGGAAGCCCCAGGACGUUGGAGGGGUAAAGUAAAAGUCCACAGUUACCGUGAGAGAAAAAAGAGGGAGAAAGCAGUGCAGCCAAACUCGGAAGAAAAGAGAGGAGGAAAAGGACUCGACUUUCACAUUGGAACAACCUUCUUUCCAGUGCUAAAGGAUCUCUGAUCUGGGGAACAACACCCUGGACAUGGCUCCAGAGAUCAACUUGCCGGGCCCAAUGAGCCUCAUUGAUAACACUAAAGGGCAGCUGGUGGUGAAUCCAGAAGCUCUGAAGAUCCUAUCUGCAAUUACGCAGCCUGUGGUGGUGGUGGCGAUUGUGGGCCUCUAUCGCACAGGCAAAUCCUACCUGAUGAACAAGCUGGCUGGGAAGAAAAACGGCUUCUCUCUAGGCUCCACAGUGAAGUCUCACACCAAGGGAAUCUGGAUGUGGUGUGUGCCUCAUCCCAAGAAGCCAGAACACACCCUAGUUCUGCUCGACACUGAGGGCCUGGGAGAUAUAGAGAAGGGUGACAAUGAGAAUGACUCCUGGAUCUUUGCCUUGGCCAUCCUCCUGAGCAGCACCUUCGUGUACAAUAGCAUGGGAACCAUCAACCAGCAGGCCAUGGACCAACUUCACUAUGUGACAGAGCUGACAGAUCGAAUCAAGGCAAACUCCUCACCUGGUAACAAUUCUGUAGACGACUCAGCUGACUUUGUGAGCUUUUUUCCAGCAUUUGUGUGGACUCUCAGAGAUUUCACCCUGGAACUGGAAGUAGAUGGAGAACCCAUCACUGCUGAUGACUACUUGGAGCUUUCGCUAAAGCUAAGAAAAGGUACUGAUAAGAAAAGUAAAAGCUUUAAUGAUCCUCGGUUGUGCAUCCGAAAGUUCUUCCCCAAGAGGAAGUGCUUCGUCUUCGAUUGGCCCGCUCCUAAGAAGUACCUUGCUCACCUAGAGCAGCUAAAGGAGGAAGAGCUGAACCCUGAUUUCAUAGAACAAGUUGCAGAAUUUUGUUCCUACAUCCUCAGCCAUUCCAAUGUCAAGACUCUUUCAGGUGGCAUUCCAGUCAAUGGGCCUCGUCUAGAGAGCCUGGUGCUGACCUACGUCAAUGCCAUCAGCAGUGGGGAUCUACCCUGCAUGGAGAACGCAGUCCUGGCCUUGGCCCAGAUAGAGAACUCAGCCGCAGUGGAAAAGGCUAUUGCCCACUAUGAACAGCAGAUGGGCCAGAAGGUGCAGCUGCCCACGGAAACCCUCCAGGAGCUGCUGGACCUGCACAGGGACAGUGAGAGAGAGGCCAUUGAAGUCUUCAUGAAGAACUCUUUCAAGGAUGUGGACCAAAUGUUCCAGAGGAAAUUAGGGGCCCAGUUGGAAGCAAGGCGAGAUGACUUUUGUAAGCAGAAUUCCAAAGCAUCAUCAGAUUGUUGCAUGGCUUUACUUCAGGAUAUAUUUGGCCCUUUAGAAGAAGAUGUCAAGCAGGGAACAUUUUCUAAACCAGGAGGUUACCGUCUCUUUACUCAGAAGCUGCAGGAGCUGAAGAAUAAGUACUACCAGGUGCCAAGGAAGGGGAUACAGGCCAAAGAGGUGCUGAAAAAAUAUUUGGAGUCCAAGGAGGAUGUGGCUGAUGCACUUCUACAGACUGAUCAGUCACUCUCAGAAAAGGAAAAAGCGAUUGAAGUGGAACGUAUAAAGGCUGAAUCUGCAGAAGCUGCAAAGAAAAUGUUGGAGGAAAUACAAAAGAAGAAUGAGGAGAUGAUGGAACAGAAAGAGAAGAGUUAUCAGGAACAUGUGAAACAAUUGACUGAGAAGAUGGAGAGGGACAGGGCCCAGUUAAUGGCAGAGCAAGAGAAGACCCUCGCUCUUAAACUUCAGGAACAGGAACGCCUUCUCAAGGAGGGAUUCGAGAAUGAGAGCAAGAGACUUCAAAAAGACAUAUGGGAUAUCCAGAUGAGAAGCAAAUCAUUGGAGCCAAUAUGUAACAUACUCUAAAAGUCCAAGGAGCAAAAUUUGCCUGUCCAGCUCCCUCUCCCCAAGAAACAACAUGAAUGAGCAACUUCAGAGUGUCAAACAACUGCCAUUAAACUUAACUCAAAAUCAUGAUGCAUGCAUUUUUGUUGAACCAUAAAGUUUGCAAAGUAAAGGUUAAGUAUGAGGUCAAUGUUUUACCUACAGAGCAAUUCAACUCAUGCUUAUUUAUAGUACUAACUUUUAAUAUGAUCUUUAACUAAAUCCUAUAUUUGAAAUCAUACACAAGGACUCAAGAGAGAUAUUGUGUAACUAGGAUGCAUUUUCCAAUGAGAUAUCUUGCAGUUUCUGUUCUGGGUAGAUUUUUUUCUCUCAUAUGCACCACCCUUACUGUAUAUUCAGUCCUAUACUCUUAUUCAGGGAUUUAACUAUGGUCGUAGCAUAGGGCUGAAGUGUUGUGAAUAUGAUGAAAAUGUGAUGAGACCAAACAAACCAUGGGGCACAGUAGAGCAUCACUCCUGCCAAGUGGUCUUUGUAUGGCAUGCUGGCUGCAAAUAAAGGAGAUCUGGGACACUUAACUAGGCUUUUAAAGUACAGACAGUGCACAGUUCUCAUUUGGGUGGAGGCUGCAUGAUCUGUGGGCACUAGCAGAGAAAGUGGUUGCCUCUGUGCAGAAUGCAUUUAUGAGUAGAGGCUCCACCUUCUCUGUCCAUGUAAACCCUCUAGGUAAUUACUGCCCCAUUCCCAGGCCACCUAGAUCUCUCUUCUCUAGUCUCCCUUAGUCUUUUCUCUUUCCUGAAGUUUAGAAAAUAACUUCUACAAUCACAGAAAGGAAAGCUUUAACUCAAACUCAAAUUACUUUCCAUUCUUCUGAGGACCAGGACUAUAAUCCUAUAAAGCCUAAAACUUGACUGCAUUUUUCUCUCUGCUCCUCUGCUAUGACAUUAUAUCCUCAAAGCUACUCAGGGUAAAUGACUUACUAAAAAAAAAAAAAUGACAGAUUGAAAAAUCAAGAAUAAUUCAUUAAUACAAAACAUUAUCCUACUACAAUUGUUUCAGGAUGUGUAUUAUUCAGAGUUCUUCAUGGCAAAUAACAAUCUGCUCAGCAAUUUAAGUAAAAAGUAAUUUACUUUUUAAUACCAUUAGGUUGCACACCGAUGCUCCAGAAUUGUGAGGGAGCCAUACUCUACAGCUAUUCCACCGAGGAUAAUACUACCAUUGUAAAGGCAUCUCACGGGAAAACAACACAGCUACCAUGAACCAGCACCAUGAUCUCUGGAUGAAAUGCUGGAAGCUUCUGCAGUGUCAGCUAUGAGUAAAUGGAUGCCACCACCUUCACAUUUUCAGUAAACAAAUACUCCCCUACCCCAUGAAAAGUUGCAUCUUUGAGCUGCUCACAUCUCCAGCUAAGCCUCACAAAAGUCAAUCUGCAGGGAAGAAUCUAAAUCAUAUGCCUACCCAUGGGAAAGUCUGAGAAUUAGAGUAUUUUUGUCUUCUACUUUUGGAGGAAGAAACUAAUAACGUGGGAAAUUUUCCUGUAUGUUUAGUCAACCAGUUUUUCCAUGCAGAUGUAUGGAGAUAAAUCUUAUAGUAGGAAUAACCUAAGACUUGAGUUAGUAUUUUUGUGUACAUCAGAUACAACACUCUUCUCAUCUUUUUUGUCAUUAUUUUUCAAUGUUGUUUUAAUCUUUCCACUGUUGUUUCAUGUCAUGCACUUUGUUAAUAUUCUUUAAGUUAUUCUUAGUUUUUAACAAUGAUACUUAAGAAAGACUUAAUAGGACUAUAGAAUAGGUACUCCCUAUUCCCCAACCCUGGGAACACAAUUUAACAUAUUAGUUCAUUUGUAUUUAAGAUCUAUCUUGUUUAUGCCUCAGUUUAGUUAUUGCUCUUACCUUUCAAACAGUUAGUAUUUUGUAUCUAGUUCUGUGAAAGCAAAAAGCAACUUUAUUCUUUCUUACAAUUCCCCUUUUACUUAAUCGGAACAUUUCUUUCCUGUUUGUUCAUUAGUCACUCUCAGAUAAAUGAAUAGUCUCUUUUUCUAAAAAAAAAAAUAACAUUUGACCUAAA